ACGGUUUCCGGUACCCGCGCCCGGCCGGCUCCGCCAGCCGUUUCGAGAGUCCGGCCGGCCCCGGCCCCGCCAUCCUCGGCUUGCGCCGCCACCACCGGGGAUCUGGUUACCUGCGCGGGUCGCCCUGCCCGGUCCCGCCCCGCCCCGCGCUCGGGUUCCAAACUCCAGGGCGGCAACCAAAGUCCGUCUCCGUUAUUUCCAGGGCAAAAUGCAUUAGGAAAAUCGCGGCUCUGGGCCCGUGACCCCGCCCUGCAGAGUCCUCCGAGGGCCGCCGGGUCCCUGCGCGGGCCACACCGGAGAGCGGAGGAAACUCCAACCCCCAUCUGUAGUUGCUGCCUCCGGGCACCGACCGCUUACCGCUAUAAAUAAUCUUUGGCCUGCGGCCACCCCGCGGGGUCUCGCCAGCCCGUGGCCCGGAGCCUGGAAAUAUUUAUUCCGAGAGGCUCCCGAGCGCGGGGUGGGGGUGUGGGGGUGGGGGUGGGGGCGGAGACUCCCGCUUCGGGUCCAGCUGUCCGGGAUACCUCUUUCCUCUCGAAAGUCAUUACCAAAAAACAGCCUCCUGGGGGUGCCCCUGGGCCUCCGCCUCCUUGCAUUAUUUAUUAUCCUCUAGGCCCUACUUCGCAGUUCUUGUGCACGCUAUGAAAAAUAAAACCUGCGUGCUCGUCUGUGGUUCUGGCUUCCAGUCGUCGCGGAGGGAGAAGUAUGGCAACGUGUUCAAGACGCAUUUGUUGGGGCGGCCGCUGAUACGCGUGACCGGCGCGGAGAACGUGCGCAAGAUCCUCAUGGGCGAGCACCACCUCGUGAGCACCGAGUGGCCUCGCAGCACCCGCAUGUUGCUGGGCCCCAACACGGUGUCCAAUUCCAUUGGCGACAUCCACCGCAACAAGCGCAAGGUCUUCUCCAAGAUCUUCAGCCACGAGGCCCUGGAGAGUUACCUGCCCAAGAUCCAGCUGGUGAUCCAGGACACACUGCGCGCCUGGAGCAGCCACCCCGAGGCCAUCAACGUGUACCAGGAGGCGCAGAAGCUGACCUUCCGCAUGGCCAUCCGGGUGCUGCUGGGCUUCAGCAUCCCUGAGGAGGACCUUGGGCACCUCUUUGAGGUCUACCAGCAGUUUGUGGACAAUGUCUUCUCCCUGCCUGUCGACCUGCCCUUCAGUGGCUACCGGCGGGGCAUUCAGGCUCGGCAGAUCCUGCAGAAGGGGCUGGAGAAGGCCAUCCGGGAGAAGCUGCAGUGCACACAGGGCAAGGACUACUUGGACGCCCUGGACCUCCUCAUUGAGAGCAGCAAGGAGCACGGGAAGGAGAUGACCAUGCAGGAGCUGAAGGACGGGACCCUGGAGCUGAUCUUUGCGGCCUAUGCCACCACGGCCAGCGCCAGCACCUCACUCAUCAUGCAGCUGCUGAAGCACCCCACUGUGCUGGAGAAGCUGCGGGAUGAGCUGCGGGCUCAUGGCAUCCUGCACAGUGGCGGCUGCCCCUGCGAGGGCACACUGCGCCUGGACACGCUCAGUGGGCUGCGCUACCUGGACUGCGUCAUCAAGGAGGUCAUGCGCCUGUUCACGCCCAUUUCCGGCGGCUACCGCACUGUGCUGCAGACCUUCGAGCUUGAUGGUUUCCAGAUCCCCAAAGGCUGGAGUGUCAUGUAUAGCAUCCGGGACACCCAUGACACAGCGCCCGUGUUCAAAGACGUGAACGUGUUCGACCCCGAUCGCUUCAGCCAGGCGCGGAGCGAGGACAAGGAUGGCCGCUUCCAUUACCUCCCGUUCGGUGGCGGUGUCCGGACCUGCCUGGGCAAGCACCUGGCCAAGCUGUUCCUGAAGGUGCUGGCGGUGGAGCUGGCUAGCACCAGCCGCUUUGAGCUGGCCACACGGACCUUCCCCCGCAUCACCUUGGUCCCCGUCCUGCACCCCGUGGAUGGCCUCAGCGUCAAGUUCUUUGGCCUGGACUCCAACCAGAACGAGAUCCUGCCGGAGACGGAGGCCAUGCUGAGCGCCACAGUCUAACCCAAGACCCACCCGCCUCAGCCCAGCCCAGGCAGCGGGGUGGUGGUUGUGGGAGGUAGAAACCUGUGUGUGGGAGGGGGCCGGAACGGGGAGGGCGAGUGGCCCCCAUACUUGCCCUCCCUUGCUCCCCCUCCCUGGCAAACCCUACCCAAAGCCAGUGGGCCCCAUUCCUAGGGCUGGGCUCCCCUUCUGGCUCCAGCUUCCCUCCAGCCACUCCCCAUUUACCAUCAGCUCAGCCCCUGGGAAGGGCGUGGCAGGGGCUCUGCAUGCCCGUGACAGUGUUAGGUGUCAGCGCGUGCUACAGUGUUUUUGUGAUGUUCUGAACUGCUCCCUUCCCUCCGUUCCUUUCGGACCCUUUUAGCUGGGGUUGGGGGACGGGAAGAGCCGUGCCCCCUUGGGCGCACUCUUCAGCGUCUCCUCCUCCUGCGCCCCCACUGCGUCUGCCCAGGAACAGCAUCCUGGGUAGCAGAACAGGAGUCAACCUUGGCGGGGCGGGGGCUGCGUCCAACCUGGAGAUUGCCCUUCCCUAUGCCACGGUUCCCACCCUCCCUCACCAGUUUGGACAAUUUGAAAUUACCUAUUGCUGCUACUUGUUCUGUCCUCUGACCUUGGGGCAAAGGAGCCCCAGGCCCUGUCUCCCCAGCAUCCUCCCUGGUGGCCCUGGGCAGGUGCACUGACACCCCCACCUUCCCAUCCCCUGCUGAACCAGGCCCUGUUACACACAGCCGCCUAAGGCCCGCGGCUCAUGUGCUGCCCGCCCCCAUAUUUAUUCACUGAUAGAGAAUCUUGGGGAUGCUGGGGUCUGGAGUGAACAUCUCCUCCCCUUCAUGCCCUAGCCUGUGUUCUAGCUGUCCUGGCGAGACUUCUGUGAGUGAAGAGGAAGGGGUCUCUGGUCAAACCCAGCCCCCAGGGCCUAGGGUUGAAAGCCUUCCCCGGCUCCGGGCAUUAUUUGGGUUUAAUCUCGGAGCCUCACUCCUGGACUGAAGUCCGGUGCCUCUGCCUUAUCCCUGGUGGAGAUGGAAUGUGGCCCAUUGCCUCCUCCCUCUCCUGUCAAAAACCCUGAUCAGGUAGAUUUGGAGGCGGCCACGAUUUCCUGUUUGGCCCCUGUUCACCCCAGUGCACUGGCCCUGACUCCAGGCGUGAGUAUGGGGAAGGAUACGGGUUCUUCUGACGGGGAGCAAGGGCCUCCGUCUUCCCUUCCUUAACUCUCCCCCUUUGCCCUCCGCCCUGAAAAAGGUGUCCUUGAAGUCCCUUCCACCUCUAUGCCACUGUCUGCUUAGCCCAGCUCAGGGGUGGGGAAGAGGCGAAAGCGUGGGGGAGGUGAGCGCAGCGGCAGUUCUGCCUCGGAGCUGAUUGCAGGGCCCUGUGUGGUCUCCGGACAGCUGCGGGAAGGCUGCCGCAGCUGAAGCUGAAGAGGCGGCUACGUGCGGUUUGUCAGGGGGAUUGGGUUGAAAACUGGCCAGUCGGGAUGACUGGGUGAAAGAGGAGUAGCUCCUGCCACUGGCGUUUUGAGUGUUGGCAAUUUGGGAUGCCUCCUGGGGAAGGUUUCCGGGCGUUUGGUGAGUCUCUAGAUUUUUCCUUGCUUUCUGUGUUUAUUGGUUUUUGAUGUUGUAAAAGCAAUGAAUCCCCUUUACAAGAAAAUCGAAAACACAGAAGAAUGAAGGACAUGCCAGUCCCCGAUCGCUGCUGUGAGCACCUCAGUGGCUCCCUCAGACCAGAUCCCGUAGGCAGCCCCACAGACCGACCCUGACCCCACUCACAGCCACCCUGAAGAUAGACUAUAGGAACGGGCCCAUACCACACAGACUGCUCUCCAAUCCCUGAGUCUCAGAUGUUUCAUUUAUUUCCUACUUUUCCACUACUAAAAAACAGUGUGGAAUAGACAUUAUUGGCAAAAUUGCUCAUCCCUAAUCCUGAAAAACAGGCCAGAAUGGGUAAAGACUUGUCAAAGCUUGCAACAUAGCUACAUGGUGCACCCGGACCUGUACCCCCUCCCCCCAACACAAAACCAGUGUCUGGGAGGUUCAUUUUCCUUUAAACUGAUCCAGCUGGCCCUGAACCAAUUGUUUUUGACUGAGUAUCUAGGAGAGCAGUAAGUGGAACUUCAGACAAGCCCACUGGGUCUGGUCCAGGUGAGGGGCAGGGGGCAUGGGGCUGGGAGGUCUCAGGGGCCUUCCCUGGGGGUGGCCAGCCUGGUAGGGGGCAGAGAAGGAAAAGCUGAGGGGGGUCCCUGUGAGGGAGGAAAGAAGGAUCAUUUGCCCCGCUGGGUCUCAAAGGCAGUGAGAAGAGAGCUGAAGAAAGCUCUGGCUGGCUGACAGGAUCCCUGUGUUGUAAUUGGUCCCUCCUUUCAGCUCUCUAGUGAGAUGCCCGUGUCUGUGCGUGUGCGUGUGUGUUUCAUACAGCUAGCAUUAGAUGGGUGAUGUUUCUUACUUAUCAUCCCUAACUAUUGCAACUUGACCUUAAAAAGACAAAACCCCACAAAACUCUUCCUGCCACGGGCUUGCAGAUUGAAGCACUUUCGAUGUUGGGCGCUGGCGUUUGUGUUCUGGGCACCACCGUGACCCUGCCCAGAUGGCUAUAAUAUUAUUUUAUACACAAACCUUUUUUUUCAUAAAUGUUAUAAUUUUGUGUCUGUCUUUAUAAACUAUUAUAAGUACUAUUUUUGUUAUAAUUCAAAAUAGAUAUUUAGUAUAAAGUUUUUGCUGUUAAAUAUUUGUUAUUUAGUAAAAUAUGAAUUUUGCUCUAUUGUAAACAUGGUUCAAAAUAUUAAUAUGUUUUUAUCACAGUCGUUUUAAUAUUGAAAAAGCACUUGUGUGUUUUGUUUUGAUAUGAAACUGGUACCGUGUGAGUGUUUUUGCUGUCGUGGUUUUAAUCUGUAUAUAAUAUUCCAUGUUGCAUAUUAAAAACAUGAAUGUUGUGCAUUUUGUGAUUUUGGAAAUACUCAAUGUGGCUCUUCUAUAGGCUUCUAGAAUAAACCGUGGGGACCCGC